AGUCCUCCGUGCGCGUCGGGCCCGAGCCCACAGAGUCCAUGGAACCCACGGAGCCGAUGGAACCUACGGAGCCCAUGGAACCUACGGAGCCCAUGGAACCUACGGAGCCCAUGGAACCUACGGAGCCCAUGGAACCGGCGCGGAGCGCGCACCGUGGGGGCGAGGCGCUGCUGCGGGAGCUGGAGGUGCUGGUGCAGGACGUGGUGAGGACGAGCUCCUGGUGGGAGCGCCACGGCGUGGACUGCGCCAUCCUCGCGCUCAGCCUCUUCGCCUUGCCGGCAGGCUUCCUGUGCCUGCGCUGGGAGAAUGCCCUGGUCUUUGCAUCCGGCAUCACCAUCUUGGGUGUGUGCCACUACACACUCACUGUCAAGGGCAGCCACCUGGCCACUCAUGGGGCCCUCACCGAGUCCAAACGCUGGAGCAAGAUCUGGCUGCUUUUCUUUGUGGAGGUGUGCACAGCCUUCACUGCAGAGCACGCCACGCAUGGGCACGUCAAGAUGCACCAUGCCUACACCAACGUGGUGGGCCUGGGGGACUCCAGCACGUGGAGGCUGCCUUGCCUCAACCGCUAUGUCUACAUGUUCCUUGCUCCUUUCCUCCUCCCCAUCGCCACUCCACUGGUGGCUGUCGAGCGGCUGAGGAAGGUGGAGCUCGGGACAGCCCUGCGGACGCUGGCCCUGAUUUCUCUGGGCCUUUAUUCUCACUACUGGCUGCUCCUGAACGUGUCAGGCUUCAAGAACCCCAGCUCAGCCCUGGGCUGCAUGUUCCUCACCAGAUCCCUGUUGGCCCACCCCUACCUCCACGUCAACAUCUUCCAGCACAUCGGACUGCCCAUGUUCUCCCGGGACAACAAGCCCCGUCGGAUUCACAUGAUGAGCCUGGGGGUGCUUAACCUGGCCCGGCUGCCCGUGCUGGACUGGGCGUUCGGCCACUCGAUCAUCAGCUGCCAUGUGGAACACCAUCUAUUCCCCAGGCUCUCUGAUAACAUGUGCCUGAAGGUGAAGCCCGUGGUGUCCCAGUUCCUACGUGAGAAGCAGCUACCGUACAACGAGGACUCAUACCUGGCUCGCUUCCAGCUGUUUCUCCGUCGCUAUGAGGAAUUCAUGGCCUUCCUCGAUCCUCAGCCAAAGGAACCUGUGCAAGACACUGGCUCAGCAGUUCCCCAGGCCACAGUAUCAGCAAGAUAAAAGUGAGUGUGUUUUGUCGGGAGGGAACUCCAGGGGAAGUGAGGGGAGAAGGUUCCCCAGGGACAGAGUUAGGGAAAGAGUAUAAAUAGCCAGCCAGGGGCGGUGGCUCAUGCCUGUAAUCCCAGCACUUUGGGAGGCCAAGGCGGGUGGAUCGCGAGAUCAGGAGCUCGAGACCACCCUGGCCAACAUGGUGAAACCCCGUCUCUACUAAAAAUACAAAAAAUUAGCUGGAUGUGGUGGCAUACACUUGUAGUCCCAGCUACUUGGCAGGCUGAGGCAGAAGAAUCACCUGAACCCGGGAGGUGGAGGUUGCAGUGAGCCAAGAUUGCACCAUUGCAUUCCAGCCUGGGUGACAGAGCGAGACUCCAUCUCAAAAAAAUAAAAAAAUAAAAAAUAAGACUCCCGUUCAAAAAAAAAAAAAAGAAUAAAUAACUUUGAAUGUGACCUUGGCUAGUUCAAACAGUUUGUUCUGUGAUGUUUAGAAGUGAACCUGGGGAUCAUCUACUGGGAGAGAGAAGAAUUUGUAGGAGGGGGCUGGGGCUGGAGGGGGUACUGGGAACAGGGUCCGGAGGACGGAUGACCUCAGAGAGGAAUGGGAGGAGGGUGGGGUGCAGAUAGAAGAGCCUGAAGUCAGGGCUGGGCAGGGCUGUGGAAGGAUGGUCUGCAGCCUGGGAGUGAGGUGGGAAUAUAAGGGAACUACCAAUGCCAGGCAGAGGAAGAGACCAAGGUGCUGGGGGACACCACUGAGAUUCAGCCCACAGUGGGUAGUAUUGAGAGAGGGCUGGGAGCUGCCCCAGCUGGGGGCUGGACUGGGAGGGUGCUAGGAAGUGCCCAGGUGGAGGCUGAGGGAGAGACAGAGAAGGAGGCCAGACCCAUUAGUUGAAAACAGGGUCUCUCACCUUGGCACUAUUGACUUUUUUUUUUAUGGAGAUGGAGUCUCGCUCUGUCGCCCAGGCUGGAGUGCAGUGGCAUGAUCUCAGCUCACUGCAACUUCUGCCUCCCAGGUUCAAGCGAUUCUCCUGCUUCAGCCUCCCGAGUAGCUGGGACUACAGGAGCCUGCCACCAUGCCUGGCUAAUUUUUUGUAUUUUAGUAGAGACGGAGUUUCACCAUGUUGCCCAAGCUGGUCUCGAACUCCUGAGCCCAGGCAAUCCACCCACCUUGGCCUCCCAAAGUGCUAGGAUUACAGGUGUGAGCCACCAUGCCCAGUCACUACUGACAUUUUAUCUGGCCAAUUCUGUGUUGUUGGGGGCUGUCCUGUGCAUUGUUGGAUGUUUAGCAGCGUCACUGGCUUCUACCUACUAGAUGCUGGGAGCUCAAGUUGUGACAAUCAAAAAUGUCUCCAGACAUUGCUGAGUUGACCCAGUUGAGAACAUGCAAGUCAUUCUCUGAGCGUGUAAUUGCCUUGUUUUUCAGUGAAGGCCUUGGAUAGAGUGAAAGGCCUCCUGACCCUGCUGAUAGGGAGACAAACUGCCGGCAAAUGGGAGCCUGGGGGAUGGGCAGAGGGGUCUGGCUACAGGCACAGGCAUUCCCUGAGCCUUGUUCCGUUGGAGAGCCCCUCUGUGGUGUGGCCUUAGGCAGCUGCACAGAGGCCACUGGUUCUUUUAUGUGCACUCUCCAUUCAUCUCCACCACACCUUCCUUUACCAAAGACCGCAGUUCCUUUAGACACCCUUUUCCAUAGCUACAGACUCUCACUAGUUCUGAAACAGCUCCCUCCAGGCUUGCGGUGGUAGUGGUUUCCAGCUGUUGCUAGCCUGGGGUGCUUCUCCAUUCCCUUCACCCUGCUCACACCUCUGUAUACAAACUCCUUCAUUAAACUGUCCUCAAUCACGCCUUUUGAGUGUGCCAUCUGUUUCUUGCUAGAAGGUUGACUGAUAGAGUGGAGUUUUGGAUCCAGGCAGCCCUCUUGGCACGAGGCAGGCUUGGCGGCUCCCCAGCCCACUGCUUUGCUAUAUGUUAUUGCUGCUCCUUGGAAAUGCAUUAGCAGCUUAGAAAUGGCCUUGAGAUCUAGGGGUGUAAUUAAUCAAACUGCUAAUUCUCCAUUUGAGAAACGCAGUGGCAGAAAAGGCCCCAGUUGCACAGUCCUGGCUCAUGAUUAAAACCAUCCAAAUACAUAACCAAUGACUCAUUGUUAUUGAUCUGGACCUGACUGGGGUAUGGGCAGCAGCUGAAGGCACUGGUGCCAGAUCUGGCUGUACCAUGGGUAUCAUGGGAACAAGUCACUCGAUUGCUUUGAGGCUCCAUUUUCUGUUUCACUUAGGAUGUGGGCUGGGAAUUUCUGAGGCCUGAGAGGUGAGGGAGGUGACAGGAGUGAAUGAAGUAUAUCCAGAUCUCUGCAGAGACUUAAGGUCUAAUCUACAGAGACAUAUGGGAGGUCAUAAUACAUAUGGAUGAUGAUAAUAAUAGCUAAUGUUUAUCUAGCAUUUAUGGAAGUUGUCUUGACCUCAUCAUCUGAUUUUAAUGUCUACAACAAAUUGCCACUAUUCAUAUUUCCCCCAAAUGUUACAGACAGUGAAAAAAAGUCCUGGAGAGAUUAAAUUUCUCAAUGUCAUAUAGCUAGUAAGUGGAGGAAGAGGGAUUCAGACCCAAUGUUGUCUGACUCUAGAAUCCAUCCUCCACCACCAGAUAUACUGCCUCUAGAUGGGGAGCCCUACAGAACUUUUUCGAUUGUACGAACUUCCAUUAUGUGCUAGCCAGUGUGUGAAGCCCUGGGGGUAUAAGAGCUGAGACUGGGUCCCCAUCCUCAUGGAGCUUAUAAUGUAGUGCAGGGGUGGUCAAACUCUGUAAAGGACCAGAUAGUAAAUAUCUGGGGCUUUGCGAACCAUAUGAUCUCUGUUACAACUACUCAAUUGUGCCAUCAAAGCACAAAUAUAGCCAUAGACAAUAUGUAAAGAAGUAAGCAUGGAUGUCUUCCAAUAAAGUUUUAUUCAAACUGAA